AAGUGCUGUCUGUGAUGUUUGGCAAGCCUGGUUUAUAUCCAUCUACAAGGUUUGCGAACCCAUGUUGCCGAUUUUUUUUUCUGCUACAGAACAACUCCCUUGGUACAAUAAAAAAGACGAGUAUUUACUUUUCAUUGAAAGUGGAGAACCUGAAAAGGAACCUGGAAAGAAGCAGCUGGAAAAGGUGAGAGGAAAACCUAGAGUGUGUGUUAUCCUGCAAGCCAAUUGAGGAAAGGAUCAUACAGAUUCUUCAGUUCAGAAGAACUCCAGCAACACUUACAUGGUGACAACACCCUCUCCCAUUCUCUGUUGUUACUCCAAAUUUUAAUUACUGGUCUCAAAACUCCUGUCUUAAUCUUAGCAGACAACCUUGGCACUUACCACUGAAUGAAAAUGAAGGCUAUUAUGUGAGAAAUACUUCAUCUUUCUCCCUUUUACCUCCUACCACCCUACAAAAAAUCCUGCAUCCAUUCCCUGUCUUUAUUCUUUGCCUCUGCUCUUGGGGGAAGAAAUUCUUUCUAUCUCUGAAUUUAAUUUCAUUCCUUUCUGUUUUCUCUGUGAUAUUGCCACAUUAGUUAUUUCUUCUCUUACCUAGGUUUUUAAAACAUGUUUUCUUUGUACUUUAUCCUUCUAGAUGCCCUAUGAAUAUGCUCAAGUUUCUUUCAUGUAAAAAAAAACACAAAAGAAUUUUAACUCUGCAUCUUUCAUGGUUGCCUUCUUAUCUCUUUACUUUCCGUAUUGACUGUGACUAUGUACUCUAGGUCUCUACAUUCUCACCUUCAAUUCAGUCUUUUAACCCACUGUCACCUGGCUUGUGCCUUCACCACUUAGCUGAGAUUGCAUUAGCAAAGGUUACUAAUGACUUCUUGAUAGCUAAGUAUAAUGGACAUUUUCAGAUCUGAACUUGACUGAUCUUCUGCAUUUAAUACUGUUGUCUGUAACAAAUCUUUUCUAUUUUUAUGAAUUUUUCAAAGGUAAGGAUAAUACUUGUUUUUUGUAGAAAAUUUAAACAUUACAGAGUCAUAAGGAUUCUUAUGCUCACCUUGAAACUUUAUUCACCCUGUGUUUCUUGACUCUUUCUUUUCUGAUACUGGUCCAGCUCUUACUACUCUGGCUAAUUUCUUAAUGCAUACUUUGUAGGUUUUUCAUUCACUGCCAACCCCUUGCAUGUUGGUGUUCAGUUGGAUCCAGUCUCAAACUUUUUUCCACUUGAAAUUUCCCUGCAAAAUAAUUUAGUUUUCUCUCAUGACCCUAGCUAUCACUCAGCGACUGCCAGUUCAGUAUUUCUAACUCAGAUCACUUUCCAAAGUGCCAAAUCCCAUACAUCCUCUUUCUUACAUGGAUAAUUGUCCAUAAAUCUCAUAGGCACUUCAAACUUCAGGAGUCCAAAAUGGAAACUAGAACCUUUUCUCGAAGUCUGUGCCAUUUUCUCUAUUACCUAGUCAUUGUCAUUGCCUUUGGUCUAAUGUGUCGAGCCAGAGCCUUACCCCAGAUUUCUUUCUCUUUUUCAUCCUUUGUAUCCAAUUUGUCACUAAUUUCAAUAGAAUCUUCUCAACAUGUCUCAUAUAUUUCUCAUUCUUUUCAUUCACAGUGUUGCUGUUUGAGUUCAGACUCUUUCAUUUCUUGUCUACAUGAAUUUUUAAGUGGUCCCAUUGCCUUCUGUCUUAACCUGACUUCAAUCCGUCUGUCACUGGGCAAAUAAUUGUCCUUAAACACUCAAAUAUGACCAUAUCAUUUUUCUGCUUAAAAUAGUGUCUCCCCGUUAGCUUCACUGUAAAUCCCACAGGAGAGAUUCCAACCACCUUAGCAUACCACCCAAAGCCUUUGUUAACUGGCCUUCGCCUAUCUUUCUAGCUGAUGUCAGGACUAGGUCUCAAGGGACUGAAAUUAGAAUGGAUUAUUCUAUUGUAAGUGUCAAGUAACAGAAAGAAGCUGCAAGUUGAAUAUGAACUGAAGUAUUUAAGAGUUUUGAAUGGUCAAAUCAGAGACACAAUGAUAUUUGAGACGUGGUUAGGGUAAGAGUAAGAAUGAAAAUUACAGAAAGACCUAAAAGGGCUGCCUAUAAAUAAAGAGGAAGGAGAAUAAGAUCAAGAACACAGAAAAUAAGAUGUUGGAAACUAUCACCAAGAGUCACUGAAAUGUCUAUAGCAUUGAGCUUAUGAUGGGUAGGUAUGUUAGGUUGACUUAAAGGAUCAGAUUUAAGAUGGAGAUUGAUAGAAAAAUCUAUUAUAUGUCUGAUCGUCUUUCUCUUCUAUAUAAAAGACUUUAUUGGCUCUUGUAUCAACUAUAGGACAAAAUUCAAGAUUUUCAAAUGACCUAAGAGGGCCUCCAUAUUUAGGCUUCUUUUUAUCUCUGCAAACUUACCUCCUUCCCCCUGCCCUCUUGAUCUUUAGGUUCCAUCAACUCUAAAUACCUGCUGCUCUUUUCUCAUGUUUCCUCUGCCAAGAUUGUCCUUAAUUUCCUCAUUUUCUGGGUAAAUGCCUGUUCAUUCCUUAAGACCCUAUACAGACAUCACCAUCUCCAGGACACUCCCUCUGAAUCCUCCUUUCUCUCAGAGUUACCCAUCCAUCCAUCCAUGCAUUUAUUUAUUUGUUUAUUAUUGAGAAAAUAUUUAUUGAGUGCUUAAUAUGGAUCAGAUUCUAUGUCAGGUAAUGGGAACACCGUGGUGAAUAAGAUAGGCCACACAUGACCUUUACCCUUCUUGGUCUUACAUUUAGCAGUGGAUACACAUGUAUAACGCAAUAAUCACAAAUAAAAUAAUUACCAAUUUCAUAAAUGCUACAAAUAAAAUAAACGAUGAACUAUCAUACAGAAAAAUGAGGAUGAGGGGUAGACAGAGAGGCAAACCACUUUAGUAUAAGGUUGAGCCAUAAAAAGUUGUUGAUCUUUAAACUGUUUGUGUCCCAUAAAAUAGUUUUACAUAGUUUAACCUAAUGGUUGACUUUCUGAGGAAUUGACAUUUAAGCUGAAACCUGAAGGAUGAGGUGGAAUUGGCCAUGCUGGCUAAGCCUAUAAUUCGGCAUGUUCCAGGAACCAAAUGAAAAGAAUUGAGAAAAAAGAAUGGAGCUUGCUUGAUAUUUCACUAGAUAAAGAAUUUAAGGCGAGUAUCUAUCUUUGUUCUCCUUGGCAACUGAGAGUCUGCCCUUGGAAACAUCAGGCACCAUGGGGAAGCGGGAUAAUCGGGUAGCCUAUAUGAAUCCUAUAGCAAUGGCCAGAUGGAGAGGCCCAACUCAAUCUGUGGGCCCAACAAUCCAAGAUUAUCUAAAUCGACCAAGACCCACCUGGGAAGAAGUAAAGAAACAAUUAGAAAAUAAAAAAACAGGUUCAAAAGCAUUAGCUGAAUUUGAAGAAAAAAUGAAUGAAAAUUGGAAGAAAGAACUUGAAAAAAGCAGAGAGAAAUUAUUAAGUGGAAAUGAGAGCUCAUCUAAAAAAAGAGAAAGAAAGAAAAAGAGAAAGAAGAAAUCUUGUCGGUCUUCAUCUUCUUCAUCAAGCUCUGAUUCUUCAAGCAGUUCUUCAGAUUCUGAGGAUGAGGAAAAGAAACAAGGAAAAAGGAGAAAGAAAAAGAAGAACCGUUCAUACAAAUCAUCCCAAAGCUCUACGCAUGAAUCAGAAUCAGAGAGCAAGGAGUCUGUAAAAAAGAAAAAGAAGUCAAAGGAUGAAACAGAGAAAGAAAAGGAUGUAAGAAGCCUCAGCAAAAAAAGAAAGAAAAGUUACCCUGAUGAUAAACCUUUAUCAUCUGAGUCCUCAUCUGAAUCAGAUUAUGAAGAGGAUGUGCAAGCAAAAAAGAAGAGAAGGUGUGAAGAGCGAGAACAAGCAAAGGAAAAAGUAAAGAAGAAGAAGAAGAAACAGCACAAGAAACAUAGUAAGAAGAAGAAAAAGAAGUCUGGAUCAAGUCACAAGUCAAGGUAACAUCAAGAAAAAAAGCAAGAAUGAGUUUGCCGAGUUCCCCUGUGUUAGUAGAAUUAUUUCUGGACUUUGAGUUGCCUAUCAAAUCCCACUGUGCCAGUAAGGGGCAUAGUGGCUGCUGGCAACUUCAAUAUACAUUUUUGUUUGUUUGCUUGUCCUUCCUUCUAAUGGUUAAUUCCUCUGAGAGCUAAAAUUCUGUUGUCAUACCAGUGAAUAAAAUGUUUGAAAUUAAAGUAAAAUGUGUUAGAUAAUGAAUAACUUUGACAAAAAAAAGUGUAUCUAAGGUUAAAUGUAUCUAAUUCGAAUACAUCUUUGAAAUAUCACCAUCAAUGAAACAUAAAUGUAAUUUCCAGACAAUUGUAGUUGGUAUUUUUGAUGCAAGGACUUAAUAUUGAUGUCUCAAAUUCCUUGCUUUUGUAAAUAAGUUUAGUUCAUUUUCCUUUUUUCUUUAAUGAAUCUUUGUUUACAUGGGGAAAGAGCAUGUGGGGUGGGAAGGGCAAGUGUUUGCUAAUCACUGUGGCUAGCUGAAUAGUGUGCCUUUGACUCUUACACAUCCUAUUUUUGCCAGAGCAGCAGCCGUCCUUUUCUUACUUUAUGAAAUUCUGGGGUGUUGUAUGCUGCUUCAAGUGAACAAGAAGGACAGGAGUUUACAGCAUAAGUAAGCCCCCAUAUCUAUGAAAUUUACCUCUUCUUCAGCACUGUUUACUAUACAGUACUGAAUAAUAUUUAGUAUUACAAUAUUACAUGAUUUGAAAUAACUUUAUACCCAUUUUGUAUGGGAACCAUUCUAAACAGACCCUGAUGUUGUUUGAUUAAGAAAUAUUCUGAAAUUUUUUUUGCAUGUUUUAUACUGUUAAGUUUUAAUUAUCUGACCAUAUUCUAUAUAACUGAUGAUCCUUUUUUAAGAUAUGAUUUAUGCUUAGGAUAUAAGUUUCAAGUUUUUAGUUUCUUAGCCUUGCUAUAUUAAUUUCAUUACUGUGUUUAAUUGCACCCUUGCCAAAAUAUUUAGCAUGUGAAAAGGUUUUUUUUAAAAAAUAUGUAAUGCCUUCAUAUUGAAGCUGGUUACUGUACGCAAGUUGAGUGCCAGACCUCUAGUACGCCGUAUGUUACAUGAAACUACUGCCAAAAUCUUAGUAAGAUUGUUGUUGAAAAGAUUGUUGUCUUAAGCAUUAAUAUUGAAUUUAUAUAGAAGUUAAAUGUAGAUGAUAAUGACAUCAUUGAUCUUCCUGUGUCCGUAUUUUCCUACAAUUUGGUGCCUUGUAUCUGUUGCUGAUUCACUUUUACCACUAGUGUAAAAAUAAGUGAAAAAAUAUUUUUACUUUACAUUUUUAUAUAUCAGAGUAACAUAAAUUAUAAAUUUGUGUCUCAAAACCACCUGUGAUGGAGGAUGUGCUAAUUGUAAUGUCAUAGGUACAAAGUAUUUUGGCAUGAUGAAAAGCUCAAUAGCUAUUGUUUUUCAAUAGCAGAUUUUAUCUCGGCUACCUUCAAUCACAAGUAAAAUUAUAAAGAUAAAAAACAUCUACAUAAACAUGUUGGCUGCCAAAUUUUUUGCAUUGGAAAUACUGGAAUCUCUCAUUAAAGUUCUUGGAACAUUAUAGUGAUGCCAUGUUAGAUUACCUUGGAGCUUCAUAACUUUAGCUUUUUCCUAAAAAUAUAUGUUUAUGCUGAUAAAAACUAUUACAUUUAUGGGAUAUUUUGUAUCCAUAUAGAGUUUUUCAGAAUUGUUCAUUAAAAUGCUUUUUAUAAGCUUAUAUUAUUUGUAGAAUAUGGCAAAAGCAUUUACAGCUCAUCAUGUAUCUAUCUGCUCCUGUUCACUUCCAAACCUCUUGUAGUUAGGCAAUGCCAUUUGACUACUUCAAGCAGAGGGAUUGUAAACAGAAGUGAUUUUCUAUUUCCAUGUUGGACUGUAAAAAGUUCUGCAUGACCCUCCAGUUUUCUUUUGCCUGUCAUGGUGACCUGAAAGCAAGAUGUUCCAAAUGGCAUACUUACAAGACGGAUGCAACCUGGGUCCUUAGGUCGCUGUUUAGAAGGGACCUGACUGGAGUGCUGAUGGACUUGCAGUAAACUUUUUAAGUGUAAGAAAUAAACUGUUAUGUGUUAAA